GCGGAGAACAAUAUGGCGGAUGGCGAGGAGCCGGAGAAGAAAAGAAGGAGAAUAGAGGAGCUGCUGGCUGAGAAAAUGGCUGUUGAUGGUGGGUGUGGGGACACUGGAGACUGGGAAGGUCGCUGGAACCAUGUAAAGAAGUUCCUCGAGCGAUCUGGACCCUUCACACACCCUGAUUUCGAACCGAGCACUGAAUCUCUCCAGUUCUUGUUAGAUACAUGUAAAGUUCUAGUCAUUGGAGCUGGCGGCUUAGGAUGUGAGCUCCUGAAAAAUCUGGCCUUGUCUGGUUUUAGACAGAUUCAUGUUAUAGAUAUGGACACUAUAGAUGUUUCCAAUCUAAAUAGGCAGUUUUUAUUUAGGCCUAAAGAUAUUGGAAGACCUAAGGCUGAAGUUGCUGCAGAAUUUCUAAAUGACAGAGUUCCUAAUUGCAAUGUAGUUCCACAUUUCAACAAGAUUCAAGAUUUUAACGACACUUUCUAUCGACAAUUUCAUAUUAUUGUAUGUGGACUGGACUCUAUCAUCGCCAGAAGAUGGAUAAAUGGCAUGCUGAUAUCUCUUCUAAAUUAUGAAGAUGGUGUCUUAGAUCCAAGCUCCAUUGUCCCUUUGAUAGAUGGGGGGACAGAAGGUUUUAAAGGAAAUGCCCGGGUGAUUCUGCCUGGAAUGACUGCUUGUAUCGAAUGCACGCUGGAACUUUAUCCACCACAGGUUAAUUUUCCCAUGUGCACCAUUGCAUCUAUGCCCAGGCUACCAGAACACUGUAUUGAGUAUGUAAGGAUGUUGCAGUGGCCUAAGGAGCAGCCUUUUGGAGAAGGGGUUCCAUUAGAUGGAGAUGAUCCUGAACAUAUACAAUGGAUUUUCCAAAAAUCCCUAGAGAGAGCAUCACAAUAUAAUAUUAGGGGUGUUACGUAUAGGCUCACUCAAGGGGUAGUAAAAAGAAUCAUUCCUGCAGUAGCUUCCACAAAUGCAGUCAUUGCAGCUGUGUGUGCCACUGAGGUUUUUAAAAUAGCCACAAGUGCAUACAUUCCCUUGAAUAAUUACUUGGUGUUUAAUGAUGUAGAUGGGCUGUAUACAUACACAUUUGAAGCAGAAAGAAAGGAAAACUGCCCAGCUUGUAGCCAGCUUCCUCAAAAUAUUCAGUUUUCUCCAUCAGCUAAACUACAGGAGGUUUUGGAUUAUCUAACCAAUAGUGCUUCUCUGCAAAUGAAAUCUCCAGCCAUCACAGCCACCCUAGAGGGAAAAAAUAGAACACUUUACUUACAGUCGGUAACCUCUAUUGAAGAACGAACAAGGCCAAAUCUCUCCAAAACAUUGAAAGAAUUGGGGCUUGUUGAUGGACAAGAACUGGCGGUUGCUGAUGUCACCACCCCACAGACUGUACUAUUCAAACUUCAUUUUACUUCUUAAGGAAAAUCUCCACAUAAUAGAAAACUCAUGGAAAUAAUAUACUUUGUGGAUGCUAAGAAGUUGAAUCGAUGUCAUUUUUAGCAAUAGUGUUGCCACGAUUUGUCUUUUUUUAUAUAAUGAACCACUCUUUUUUAACUUUGUAACCUUCCCUUGAAGACAGAAUUUUGGUGUUGGUGCUUGUAAGCAUUUUCAUUAAUAAUAUGAGAAAUGAUACCUGGAGAGAGAGAUUAUGAGCAAAUGUAUUGCUUCUUUUAGAGGAGGAAGCAUACAACCUCUUUUGUGUGAAUUUUGUUAUUAUGGUCAAAGAAUGCAUUCCUAAGUUUUCAUUUGAGUACCCAAAUACACAAAAGGUGUCCCUUUAAGGAAAAUAAAGAAUUAAGUUUUAAAUAACAUUACAUUUUACAAUCUGACAUCUGGAGUAUAUUGAACAUAGGCUAUUUCUUGAUAUAACACUCAUUUAAUUGUGGCCAUCCAAAUGAAUAUUAUUGCAGAAUUUAUCUUGUUCAUAAUGAUUUGUAAAUGGUGUUAUAGCUGAAUACCUGUGCAUGAAAAUGGGCAAUAUUUUCAUCUGUUUACUUGUAGUGCCAUAGAGGCCAAUAUGCACAAUAUUAACUAAUGCCAAGACAUGGCUGUUUAAAAAAUUUAAUGUUCAAACAGUUAUCACUGAUGCUUUUGCACUAUUUAUUAAUAAAAUCAUAUAUUGUGUA